AGCACUGAUACAGUUCACGUCUCUCCAGUGAGUGGCAUCUCCUAUCUGCUCCUUCCUGCCUGAGCUGGCCAUUUGUACCCUGCAAAAGUCCGAGUUCCUGCCCUGCCAUCCUUCCUGGCCUGGAAAUGCACAAGUGUCACUCACAAGUGCUUAAUUUUCCUGAAGCAGGGAAUUGGGCCCGAGUUAAUUUCUAAAUGUCUAUUCCAGACCCUUCUCCGACCAGGAGGCUGUGGUUCAGUCCCUGGCAAACGAGCAGUGACGCUGAUUAGCAAGUGCUCCGAUGGGCAGCCUGCCUUUCCUGGGGCACCGGCUGGGAACACCAACACCUUUCUUGUGAGCACAUCUCCCCCUUUUGCCUAUAAAAACAGUCUAUAAGAUGGUAAAGAUUGGGCCAUAAAACUUCCGUUCCAAUCCAUUCAGCAUCAAUAGCCUGAAAAAGUGGGAGCAGCAGAGGGGCCAAGAUUAGCUUUGAAAUAAAUAAAUCUUAGGAGGUAAGAAUGAAUUUCUUGGUCGAGGGUGGUGGGGAAGGGAUGAGGUGCGACCAUCAUAGCUCAAGUCUCCCAUUAUCCUUCAGUAUCUGUUCUUCGGGGUCCUGGUCACACCAUGGGCCUGGGCAGGGAAGUCACCUGGUUUGGCUGAAGGAUGGGGCCUCAGGCCCCUCCCCCUAUUGCUCCAGACAUGGAAUUUACAACAAAGAAGUAGAGAGACAGGAUAUGAGGGUAGGAAGGUACAAGGAGGCAGUUGUCCAAUUUUCUAAGAAAAUGGAUUUGUUCGAGUGAGAAACUAAAAUGUCAGGUUUAGGAAGGCGGCUUUGGAUUGAAUGACUACUAGUGUCUCAGGCAGAACUGUCAGCCUGGGAGGUGUCACAUGAUUCCUGUGUCUUCACAUGAUCACUGUUUUGGGGGGGUGGGGCCAAUCAUGUGAAUUAUCCUGGGUGGGGGAGGCAAGAGAAGAAGUUUCUAAAGAUUGCUUUUAGCACAAAUGCUGCCAAAGGGAAAUUCUAAAAAGAUCCCAGUGAAGUCACCAACCUAUGUUUUUGGACCCAAUGUGAGGCCUGUUUCCUAAAACAACUGCACUGAGGGAGAUUCUGAGGCUGGGAGAAGGGCAAGGGACUGAGGCCUGGGGACACCUGGCACCUGAUUUUGUGUCAGCAGGGCCUGACGCUGAACCCGCAGGAUGCCUGCUUGGCCCCAGGUAGGCCUUGAGACCUCUGAGUCACCCCCCAGGCCGACCUCAGAUAAACUCCCAUUCAUUUCUUCUCUCUGGCCUGGAGGAGGCCAAGCCAAGUUGCAGUUCAGGCUCUGGGGAGCAGCGGGGCCCCCCAGUGAACCUCUCACCGUUUGGUAGAGGGUGGCACUCUGGGGGCUCCUCUGUACUUUCCUAAAUGGUAAAGUUAAUCUCACUUCCUCUUUCGUAAGAAGAGAAAACGGGGCGGGAGUGCUUUGGCUCAACACAUCAGGCUGUUGGAAGUUCCUUUAAAGCCAUAGUUUUCUCUGAGUACUUUCUGGCCUUUACCAACCCCUCGGAAACUCACGGUAAUUCACGUCUGUACUUGCAGUCAUGCAGCACCUAUGCAGUGCUGGUGUGAACCAUGUGUUGAGAGAAGGGAGGAAAACCAACAUUCAUUAGAUAGUUAAUGGCGUUCCAGGCCGGAUGCUGCUCCUGCGUCGUCUCACCCGCAAGACAUGGAUUGGCUCUUCUCCCCAUUCUGCAGAUGCAGAAAAUCGAGUCCCAAACUGGGGAACUAACUUAUAAGUGAUAGAGAGGAGCCAGGAUUUUGGAUGCUGGCCUUCCUGCUGGGUGGCUUCUAGGGAAGAAGCUCAAUGACUUAAUCAGGAUGAUUUAGUCCAAGCUGGAGAGGGAGUGAGAGAGGCCCCUUUCUGGCCUUGGGUGGAGGACUGUAGAAGAGUUCUUUCUCUGGGCAGAAGGUUUUGAUGAAGUCACAGGCAUUUCUCUGAAAGCCUGCUGAGGGUGGAAAUACUGACAGCCCCUUGGUCCUCACCAGUAACAACACAUGAGAGGUGAUGUGGCUCCUGUGAGAGCCCCCCAUCUGGGCUGCUGAGCUCUGGAGCCCCCAGAGCUGGAAUAUUCCUCCCUGCAUCUUCCUGGUGCCCUUUGCGACAGAUGGAGAGGGGGUGUGCGAGAGGAAGGGAGUCUAAAAGUGUUGUACGGAUCCCACACGCGCUCGCUUGCUGCUUCCAAUGGCUCCGUGCGACAGGUUAUUUUCUUAUUUGUAGUCUUGGACUGACGGAAGGUUUCCCCCCUCUCUCUCUCUUUUUAAAUGUGCUCAGAUUUCUGGCCUGUCAACACAACUCAGAUCAUGUCACUCCCCAGCUCAAAACUGUUGAGUGGGUCCAAGUUUUCUUUAAAAAAAAAAAACAAAAAAACACAAAGCUGCCGUGAGGCCUGGGCUUCCUCCCUGCCAGGCCUGAUUUCCAGCCACAUGUUUUCCAACAAGCUGACCUGUUGAGAUGCUGCAGGAUAACCAGGCUUCCUCCCUGCAGACCAGAGCUUUGCUGGCUACUCAGCCACACGAGCACCCCAAAGACCCUGAGAAGCCCUGCAAUGUAGAAUCCCGAGCUGGGUCACAUUUACUCCAGUGUUCCCUGAACUUAUGAACGAGAGGCAUUUGAUUUGUAGUAUGCCCGUUAGCAUGUGGCCUCUCUCCGUUUGGUAAACGGUUUUCUACAGAUCCAUGCCCUCAGCUGAACUCUCAGCUCUGUGCCUUGGCCCGUGCUGUUCCUGCCAUCAGAAAUGCCCUCCCUGUACCUCCUUGUCUUCCUGUGUCUGAAUCCUACUCAUCCUCCGAGGUUCAAUUUAAUGUGCCUCCUGGGGAGAGGUCAGAGGAGCCUCUCCACGCAGACACACACCCUGGCCUAGCGCUAAGAUGGUGCUAAGACCCCUGGGUGUUGAUCUGAGCCCUGCUACUGACUUGGACAAUUUGCAGGAAUCUGUGUCUCAUUUUGCUCAUCUGUAAAAGAGGAAUGGUAUUAACCACUCUAUUGCAAGGAUUAAGUUAAUUAAUGCGUGUAUAAUGCUGGAAGCCAUGCCUUGUAUGUAGUAAGCACUCAAUACAUAUUAACCAGUGUUGUAAUUAGCAUGGCUUUAUUCUGGUUUGAUUCCUCUUUUUUAACAAUUGGGACGGAUUUUCAUAAAACAUCUAACACAGUUGCUUACACAUAGGGGGUACUUAAAAAACAGCAAAGGCUGUUCAGUGAACAAAUGUCCUUCAGCUUGAUAUUUUCCUUGUAGCUUUUUUUUUUUCUUUUUUUUUUUUUUGAGAUGGAGUUUCACUCUUGUUGCCCAGGCUGGAGUGCAAUGGCGUGAUCUCGGCUCAACGCAACCUCCGCCUCCUGGGUUCAAGCGAUUCUCCUGCCUCAGCCUCCCGAGUAGCUGGGAUUACAGGGAUGCGCCACCAUGCCUGGCUGAUUUUGUAUUUUUAGUAGAGACAAGGUUUCUCCGUGUUGGUCAGGCUGGUCUCGAACUCCUGACCCCAGGUGAUCCACCUCCCAAAGUGCUGGGAUUACAGGCUGAGCCACCGCACCACCCAGCUGUCCUUGUAGCUUUUAUGCUGUUGGGGGAUGGACAAGUUGAGUAGAAACCCAGGCUAGAGUGAUUUAAUUGCCUGUUACUAGGGACUGAGUGCUGUGGGCACAGCCUGCCUCUAGGUGUCUCUAUCUGGAUCCACAGGUCUGCAGUUGUGGAUUCCCGGACCUGCAAAGCAGUAGGGGGCCUGAGAGAGCCCUCUGUGCUUUCAUCCAGUGCCUUAUGGUGCGGCCAGAAGAACAGAGAGAAAAAAACUGGCCGGGCCCACGCGGGAGAUCCAUGGCAAGGCCCGGCUGGAACGCCAAGCCUCCUGUGGUCCAGGCCAAGGCUUUUAAAAACUGGGCUGUGCUGGAACUUUCCACUGUUUCAGCCAGAAAUCUGACAGGAUCCCGAAUUCCCCGGGAAAACACUAAAGUAAUACUAAUAGGAACCAUCUGGGUUCUCUGCUUCCUGGGCUCAGCACUUGGUGUGUGUGACCCUGGUGGUACUCACAGCCACCUGGCGAUGCACGUCGUUAUCUUCGGACCCGUUGGAUCUGUGAGGAAACUGAGGCUCUGAAUGGUGAAGCAGCUUGCCCAAGGCCACACCGUAAGCGCCAGAUGUGGAUAACCACUGUCGGCCUAAUCACAGAGCCUAUGUGGUUAACUGUUGUGCCAUUCCUUAGCCGUCACUGAGGCUUGCUUGACAGGUAGGGAAACUGAGGCCCAGUUGUGCUGGCACCCUGCUCCCUUAGUGCUCCUCUCAUUUUUGUUUUUGUUUUUUCUUCCUUUCUUUCUUUCUUUUUUUUUUUUUUUUUUUUUUUUUGAGACGGAGUCUUGCUCUGUCGCCCAGGCUGGAGUGCAGUGGUGCGACCUCGGCUCACUGCAGCCUCUGCCUCCUGGGUCCAAGCAAUUCUCCUAUCUCAGCCUCCCCAGUAGCUAGGACUACAGGCGCACACCGUCACGCCCAGCUAAUUUUUGUGUUUUUAGUAGAGACUGGGUUUCACCAUAUUGAUCAGGCUGGUCUCAAACUCCUGACCUCAGGUGAUCCUCCCGCCUCGGCCUCCCAAAGUGCUGGGAUUACAGGCGUGAGCCACUGCACCCGGCCUCCUCUCGUAUUUCUAUCAGUGCACCUUCCUAUGAGGUGGGGGCAGUGUGUGUCCCCAAGGUGUGUCCCUGUCCCCAUACUAGAGAAGGAAGCAUCUAUUUUCACAGCUGAAACUGCUUUCCUGUUAACUGCUGGUGUUCCUGGGAUGGGUAUUCUGAUGAAGCCCUCCACGAGAUGGAUUUUCCCUGCCAGGUGUCUUGCCAGGCCCUCAGUCCAGAGAGAUGCAAAACAGCUGAGGUGGAAGUCGGAAAUGCUGCAGAAUUGGUUCUUUGUGUCUGUAAGAUUUCCUGGCACAUUCGUUCGGGGGCGCAGGGUGUUAGAUGGCUGCAGAUUAGCGCCAAGAGCCCAAGGAGAUCAGGUGCUCGGAUCAGGAGGGAAAUUGGAAGCCGGGAGUGAGCGAUGGGCCUCCCAGCCAGGAGGGACGGCUGGAGCAGGUGGGCGGUGAUACCAGCGCCGUUUCUACAGCUCCAUUCUUCAGGCCGACCGUCGGUGUUCUCCAGAAAUGGAAGCCCGUGGUGGAAGGAAAUACUAGGUACACGAUGUGCUCGGCACAGGCUGAGCCUUGAACAUGUGUUAGCUCUUCCUUAUCUUUUUAUUUUGGAAAAUUUCAAACAUAUGCAAAAUGAGAAGGAAUGAUGUAAUGAGCCUCAGCUUUGACACUGAUCAACUCUAUACCAUGCUUGUCCCCUGCCCCUAUUUUUGCUAGGGAGAGGAGAAUCGGGGAGUAUAUAAAGCAAGUGCUAAACAUGGGGUAUCAUUUCACCCACCGAUACUCUCUCCACAUCCCUUCAUGUGAGCUGUUACCUGACCCUCACCACGAGCCAAACAGUAUGGCCCUUCAUCCCCACUUUACAGAUAAGGCAACUGAGGCUUCCCAAGGCCAAGUGGGGCUCAUCCUUAGGCCACACAGCCAGUGAGAGGUAAAGCCAGGCUCCACUCCUCACUUUACCCUUAACCACUUUGCAGUCAUUAUUAGGGUCAUUUUAAUUGUAAAUAUUCAUUCAACAAAUAUUUUUGAGCACCUACUAUGUGCCAGGGAUGGCUCUAGGUGCUUGGAGGAUACAAAUGUGAACAAGACAGACAAAAACACCUGCUCUCGUGCAGCAGACAUUCUAGUGAGGAAGAGAAAAACACACCCAAGUAAACAAAUGAUGCCAGGUAGCUGGGGAGAAAAGCAGGAGGAGGGAAGGGAGAAGGUUAGUCAGGACAGAGGGAGGGCCGCUCUAAGGAGCAGAGGCCUCAAGAAAAUGUACAAUUAAGGCCAGGUGCGGUGGCUCACGCCUAUAAUCCCAGCACUUUGGGAGGCUGAGGUGGGCAGAUCACCUGAGGUCAGGAGUUUGAGACCAGCCUGGCCAACAUGGCGAAAUCCCAUCUCCACUAAAAAUACAAAAAUUAGCCGGGCAUGGUGGCGUGCGCCUGGAAUCCCAGCUACUCUGGAGGCUGCGGCAGGAGAAUCGCUUGACCCCAGGAGGCAGAGGUUGCAGUGAGCCGAGAUUGCACCACUGCACUCCCGCCUGGGUGACAGAGCAAGACUCUGUCUCAAAAAAAAAAAAAAAAAAAAAGAAAAGAAAGAAAAGAAAAUGGAGGAGUAGCCACGGGGGAUAGCAAGAGCCCUCCAUGUGGGAGGAAUGGCAGAUGCAAAGGCCCUGAGGCAGGAAUGAGCUUGUAUGUUCCAGGAAUUGCAAAGAGGCCAGUGGGGCUGGAGUGAAAGUAGAAGAGGUGGGGGAGUGAGCAGAGGUCAGGGCCAGACCAGCAGGAUCUGGCUCAUUGAGCACCUAACAUGGAGCAUGUCUGGCUUGUGAGAGGAUCAUUAUGCAUUCUCUCAUUUAAUUCUCACCACGGGUUCUGUAAGAUGGGAAAUACCGUUAAUCCAUUGGACAGAUGAAGAAACUGAGACUCAGAAAGGUAAAGUGACUUGCCUAAGGUCACACAGCUUUUAUGUGCAGAACUAGGAUUUAGGUCCCUGAAUGCUGCAGCAUCCCCAUUGCUGCUUUCCGCAGCCGUCCUUGCCCCCUUCGGGCUCUUCACCCAUAGCAGCUGGAGUGAAUCAAGUCAUCUUUGGUUCUGCUGGAAACCUUUUUCGGUUUCCAGCAUGGCAUUUCUGGACCACGUCUGUCUCUUCAUCCUCACCUCUUACCACUCUCCUGCCUCCUUGGGCUUCAGCCUUGGCAGCGUCCUUUCUGGCCCUUCACCAGCUUCUUUCCCACCCGAGGGCCUUUGCACUGGCUGUCUCUUCUACGGGAGCAUCUUCCCUGGUCUUCACUUCCUUUGGGUCUCAGCUGCCACCUCCCUUCCUUGGAUGCUGUCCCAACCACCCCAUUCCAAAAGAGGUUAUCGCUUGUGAUUCUCUAUCACUGGGCCAAAUCUGCCUGUUGCCUAGUGCUCCUAGCCCUUUCUAUAUUAAUUCAUUUCAUUAUUUCAGCCCUGUCUCCUCCACUAGGAUAUAAGCUGCACGAGAGAUGGGCUAUGUCUCUUACUCACUGUUGGGCCUCCCAGGACCUCAGCACAGGGCCUGACACACAGUAGGUGGGUUAAUAGAUACUGAUUGAAUGAAAGAACAAGGUGGGUACUAAAAUCCCCCUUUUAAAGAGGAGGCUUGGAGUUAUGAGGUUGUACGAGCAAAGCUUAUUCCCUAACUACCACAGUCCCCCCCCUGCAGCCAGGGCCGGGAUCAUACCACAAUUCCCUGCCCAUCAAGCUGUCAUGAAUAGCCCUAAGAUAUCAGGAAGCACAAAGAUAUCAAUGCCAGGAGGGAUAGGAGGAGGCGGCCAAGAAACCCCGGAAUUUGUACUUAAAAUUCUGGCUACGCAAACUGCUUGCCCAACUUUAGACACCAUGAUGAAUGAUCAGGUGCUGCAACCAUGAAACAUGACGUAAUUAGUGCUGCACUCUUGGCUGGGGGUUGGCUUGGAGGCCCCACCUCGAGGUUAGCCUCCCCCAGAGGGUCACUGCACGAGGCAGUCUGGUGCGGGGUGGGGGUUACAACAGAGGGAGGUGGAAUCAGACCACUCGGCAGCCCUGUGACCAUGGCCAAAUGGUUGUACCUCCCAAAGCUUCACAUCUGGUCCUCCGUGAAAUGGGGGUGGCGACAGCCCUGUCUUACUGGGCUCCUGCAGAGGUUCCAUGAGGCCUGUCUUGCUCUGGGCAGCGUCGAUGCUUAUUAGCUAUUGUUACUGCUGUUAUGUGAUUGUCAUCGUUUUAUGGUUUGGGAAUUUUAAAAGCUCCAUCUUUUGCCAGCGGGGAGACCUGGAACCCACUCCUCUGCCCCCUCAGCCUCAGUUUCCCCUUCUGUGACCGGGAGGCUUGGCUCGGCUCCUCUCUUGCAGGUCCCUUCCAGCCCUGAUGCUCCAGCCUGCAUGUCCUCCUGGCCCUUUGUCCUGAUGACUCCACAGACUCCUCUGGGAGGAGAGGCCAUGGAGGGGCUUCUGCUCUGGGGCACAUUCCUGAAUUGGAGUCCAGCAUGUGCCGCUUACUGGCUGUGUGCUCUGGGGCAGGUGUCUUCCCAGCUCUGAGCCUCCGUUUCCCCAUCUGCAAAAUGGAACCGCUAACACUGUUUCCUCCCAAAUGGGUGACUGUUGAGGGUUAAGGAAUUAAGAGCCGUGGAAAGUGCUUUUGCAAGCUGCAAAAUGCUCUAUAAAAGGAAUCAGUGAAUAGUGUCAGCUUGGGGAAAAAUCCCGUCAGUCCGGAGACUGUCUGCUGCCGGCAGUGUGCUGAAACCCUGGCAAAUGUCGUUUAAUAAAUGCGUGUUGCUUUUAAGAGGGCCUUUAUCUCAGCUGGGAAAAUGUGUGCGCAUCCUUGGCAACCUGAGAAUCCAGAAGCCUGAACUGGAGGGGACCUGUCACAGGGAGAGGCGAUCGCAUGGGGUGGCUCCAGCCUCCAGUGUUGGAAUCCCACCUCUGCCACUUACCUACCUCUCCAGACUCUGCUUCCUCAUCUGUAGGAGGGGACAGUGACAAUAGCACCUGCCACUCUGGGCCAGGAUGUCCUGAGGGCUAAAUGAAGGCUUCUGGUUAUCUGGCCUAACCCAUGCAUUUCCCCCAUGAAAGUGUGGCUGUGCAGCACCAGGGCCUGUCUCAGGGCAAUGGUUGGGGCCUGGAGAUUGGGAGGACCUCCCAACCUCAGCCUCUCCAGGCCUUACUCCAGGCCUCAGUUUCUUCCUCUGCAAAAUGAGGAGGAGGAAAGGUCCUUAGGUUGUCAAGGCACCAAGCCUAGUAGAUGUCAAUGUCCUCUACCUGCUCUCUCAGCCUCUGCCGGUCCCCCGAAGCCUGUUAAUUCUAAAGGAUAUUUACACAGAUUUGCAGUUCUUUUCCUGCCACUUUGCAAACAGGGUCACACUGCAAGCAUCGCUUCAUCACCUCCAGGUUUCAUCUGAACCCAGCAAAUGCUCCAUAGGGCUCCCAGUGCCGCCUGUCCCCGCUGCCUCCUUGCCAGCAGUGUGCUCAGCCUGCUUACAGGCCCAUGCCAGAGGGGCCUCAUGCAUGCAUCAAGGCAGAGCUGGUUCUGCCUCGGAGAGGAUCCCGAGCCUCUCAGGCUUAAGGACGUGGUCAUCUGUCGCCCCCUUCAUCUUUAGACACCCAUCUGCAUGGUGACAGCUGCUCUGCAUUGAGUACUUACUCUGUGCCAGGCACGCUAGCCCGUUUCAUCCUCAGAACAACCCUAGUAUUGUUAUCAUCAUCAUCAUCAUCAGACCCAUUCUACAGAUAAAGAGCCAGAGGUCCAGAGUGGGCGAGACAUUCCCUGGAGUCUCAUGGGUAGCAGAGUUGGAAUCCAAAUCAAAACAUACUUUCAGCCAGUGCCAGGCACUGCUCCAACCCUGGGGAAGAAAACUCAGUUCCUGCUCUCAAAGGACUUAUAAGUGAGUCUAUGACAGGGAGAUGAGCGCUUUUAAAAAAUUAACAAGGAAAUGCGUAGCUUUUUGAGUGAGGAUGACAUAUCGAACAAUGAAGCAGAGCCAGGGACAUUGAGGUGGGUAGUAUUUUAGACAGAAUGGCCAAGGAAGGCCUCUCAGAUAGGCCUGAAGGAGAGGAGCGAGCCAGACAUGUAGAUAUUUAGGGAUGAGAGUGCCAGGCAGAGGCAAUGGCGAGUGCAAAGGUCAUGUGGUGAGUGGAGAAUCUGGCACGAUUGGGGGAAAGCAAGGCUGUAGGCCCCUGGGGCCACUGUAAAAAUUCUGGGUUUCACUCUGAGUGCAGUGGGGGCUGUGGGAGGGUUUUGCACAAAGGAGGAACGUCACCUGACUUAGGUUUUAGAGGCUUCUCUGGCUGCUGGGGGAAUGUGGCUGGUAGAGAGGUGAGGCAGAGGCAGGGAGGUCAGCGUGGAGGUUCAGUCAGGGUGGUAAGAAGAGGUCAGGGUCUGGCCAUGUGUUGGAAGUUGAGCCAGCAGGAUCUACUAACAGAUGGGUUGUGGAACACGGAUGAAAGGGAGUCAAGGAAAUGUCUCAUUCUGAGUCCAGCACUUCUAACCACAGAGCCUCUGACCUGGGGAGGGAGGGGGCUGCAUUUCCUGUUUACAGGUGAGGAAACAGGCUUAGAGAAAAGCAACUUUGCCAAGCACCGUGCUACAGACAAGACAUAAAGGUCAUCUGGCCCCAGAACCUGAGCUCUGGACAGUCUUAGCACCUUAGAAGUUUACCUACUGCAUGGAUGGGGCCACCAGAGUCUGCCCCUUCCCUGCAGGGAUGUGGCACAGCACUGAGUUCUCAGAGCUACCCAGGGCAAGGGUGAAGGAGUGGGGACCCUGAGCCCCUGGGCCAGCUGUCAGCUUAUUUACCAGGCCACACGCAUCCCCAUUUUUGGUGGCUUCAAUGCAGGUAGCAGUUUCUAUCACAGCACCUGGUUUGUCCCUGCCCAAUGGGUGUAUCCAGUGGUGCCGGCAGAAUGUUCCCAGUGCUGGCCUGCUCUUCAGAUGGGCAACCGAAACCAUCCUUCAGGGCGCUAGGUUAGCCCAGUCCCAGGUCCUCCCCAUCUCAGCUUCCUUACAGCCAGUGAGCAUGUUCCAAGGACUCUACCCUGAGUCCUGUCACCUCUGCGUCUUUGCUCAUGUGGUUCCCUCCUCUUGGAAUGCCUUCCUUCAUCCCAGCCUCUGUCAGCCUUUAAGACCUAGCUCAGGGGCCACCAGCUCCAGGAAGUCUUCCUGGGUUUCACUCUCUUCCAGAACCCCAUCCCUAAACCUCCUCUUGCAACACCGAUCGCCAUGUGCGUGGUCAUUGCUCAUGUCCAGGACGGCCCCACAUGCUAAGAUAGUCUCAAGGGCAAGGGCCUGUCUUACUUGGCUCUGUUUUCUGUGGUAUCUAGGACAGGGCCUGGCAGCAGAGUGAGGUUUGAGAGGGCAUGAAUGAAUCAUUCUGACUCCAGAGGAAAUCACUGUGUAGUCCUGGCUGUUGGAGCCCCAAGCUCUCUUCUUGGGAACUGUGGCAUCCAUGCAGCCAUCCACUGGUGCAGCCCCGGCCAUGAAUGCAGCCCCAGCUACCUUUCGCCUUCCUGCAUGGGGUCAUGGGCUCCAGCAGAUGGUUCUGGGCUAGCCUGUUGACAGCUGUGCCCUGUGGCCAGCACAUAGUAAGUAGGUGCUCUGGAAAGGUUAGCACCUCCUAUCAAGGGCACGACCCUAGACAGAUACCACACAGGGUGUUGACCGCCAGGAGCCCAUGGCAGACUUGAGGGAAGUGUGUCUCCUCACAUCCUCCAUCACCCUUGUGCUUGUGGAAACUUACACAGCAACCUCAUCUAUUCCAGGCACAUGCCCAGCUGGACACACUCCCGAACACAGGCACACGGACACCUGGGGUGCACACAAAUAGUGGCAUGUGCAUACCUCCCUGCUUGUCAAUGCACACACCCUCAUAGUCACAUUUACGCAUACAGCACUCUGUCACACACGUGCCACCCCCCACACACACCCUCUACACACACAUACACACCACACUCACGUGCAUGCCGCUCCUGCAUCACUCUCCCACACACUCACACCCUCCCACACAUGCCCAGGCCACCAUGAUUCAGACACUCUCCUGCACACAAUUCACAUGCCCACGCCCAUGAUCCCUAGCCCCCCAUUCAGACACAGUCCUGUGUUGCACUCUGACAUAUUCCGGCACACAGGCACCGUCUCUUUCACACUCCUCCUUGUGCCCACCCAUGUGUACAUGUGUGUGCAGAUGCUUAUGCUCUGUACACGCAUACAUGUAUGUACACACGUGUGUUCUCGUGUGCAUACUCUUAUGCACCCUCAGCACACUCAUGUUCACAUGUUCCAUUGUACAGCCCUGUACUACAUCCUGUGUGCAUCCGCUUUAAUGUACACUCAUGUUCACGUGUUCUAUUGCACAGCCCUGUACUAUAUCCUGUGUACAUCCUCUUUAAUGCACUCUUAAUGUUCACAUGUUCUCUGCAUAGCCCUUUAUUACAUCCUGUUUGCAUCCGCCUUAAUGCACAUUUAUGUUCACAUGUGCUAUUGCAAGGUCCUGUACUACAUCCUGUGAGCACCCUCUUUAAUGCACACUCUUGCACUGCAUACUCUGGCACACAGCAUUAAAUCACACCCAGAAGAUAGUAGAGGCAGCCCCCGAUGAGGAGCUGCUAUAAGUGCGGGGUGGAAAAUCGCAGCCUUCUGAGGAUGGUGAAUAACAAUAAUGAUGAGGGAAGAAGGGAGCCGGGUAUCACUGCAGCCACUUUAGAAUGUUGAGCCCUGUGUACUGCCAGAGCUCCAGCCAUAGCCUCCCAGACCCUGGGGGUCCUUGAGUACAAACAAAGAAUCUACAAAGAAUCCAAACAGGUGGCCUCCUGCCUGUCCCUGUGGCUUGUGCUGUGGUGACCCACUGCUUCCGGGGGAUGGGCAAGCUCCCAUGCAGUGGCAGUGAGCACCCGCCUGGGCAAGGCUGGUUCUUGGGAAAUGUGCCUGUUGGCUUCCUUCUCCCCACCCCUUGAGACAGGCUUCUGGAAGACUCACACCCCAGGGUAAGGCAGCCCUCCCCAUCCCCGCCUCAAGCUUCAGUUCUAAGUUGAUUUUUUUUUCUAUUAGAAAAAACAUCCAUGUGGGCAGGGCGCAGUGGCUCAUGCCUGUAAUCCCAGCACUUUGGGAGGCUGAGGCGGGCAGAUCGCCUGAGGUCAGGAGUUUGAGACCAGCCUGGCCAACAUGGUGAAACUCCAUCUCUACUAAAAAUACAAAAAUUAGCCAGGUGUGGUGGCAGGCGCCUGCAACCCCAGCUACUUGGGAGGCUGAGGCAGGAGAAUUGCUUGAACCCGGGAGGUGGAGGUUGCAGUGAGCCGAGAUUGUGCCAUUGCACUCCAGCCUGGGUGAUGAGAGUGAGACUUCGUCUCAAAAGAAAAAAAAAGUAUCCAUGCUAAUUUUUUUCACCCUUUAUGAAAUAUUUUCAUCUUUUAAUCUCAAAAGCCACACACAUGAACAUUGUUUUUUAAGAAAUCAAAUAUAUUUUCUAAAUCCCAGUGGUCAGUUCUCAGCCCCCAUCUUAUUGCAUCUCUCAGUGGCAUUCAAUGCAGGUGGUCACACCCUCCUUGGCCAAUUCAAAGAAGAGAAAGGAGAUGUGGCGGGAGAAGCAGGUCACAGGAAGGGGCCGGGAGAUGGGAUCUAAGAUGCCAGCAGGAGCCUCUUGCCCAGGGGGGUUAGGUACAUUCCAGAUGUAAUCAUUUGAGUGAUUUCUUUGAAAUCCAUCUUUGCCUCGAGGGUGGAAGCUCCAUGAGGCCAGGGACACAGCCAUUUCACAGCCCUUAGCUCAGGGCCUGGCACAGGGAAGGAUCCAGAAUGCAGCACUGACCGCACUUGCUGUGGACACUGAGUUCCUCUUACAGCAAACAUAUGGUGACCACCCACUGUGCUGACUGCUCCCCUUAGGAAACGUGUUCGUGUGUUUUGUUUCAUUACUUUUUAACUUUUUUCCAAAACCAAUAAAUGUUCACUGCAAAAAAAUACAAUAUAUGAUGUAUUAUAAAGUAAUAAGAAAACAUGCCGACCCCAUCCUACCUCAGUCCCAUUUCCCAGAUGCAACACACCACAGCAUGCCAUGUUUAACUUAUCAUCCUUGCAGACCUUUUUCUCUAGACAUGCGAUUGACCAAUCAACAAAGAUUUAUCGAGCGUCUACACUGUGCCAACCACAGUAGCAGGAGCUGGGGAAACAGUGAACAAAACAGACUAAAUCCCUGGAGGAGAGGUUCAUUUAAACAGUACACAUACGGUAACAUACAUCAUUACAUGUACAGGUUUUUUAAAAAACAAAAUGAGAUACUAUAAAUAUUCUUUUGUGUUCAUCCAAUUUAGAGAAGCUGAAACAAUGCCCAAAGUAGGAGGGGAAAAAAAGAGAAAAACCUCAUGAGGUUUAGAUUCAUGAUCCAAAGAGAGUUACAUUUUAUAGCUUUGUUUAAUACCCUCCAGUUGUUUAUAUAUAGUUUUAUUUUACAAAGUCAUGAUCAUACAGAGGGUAUAGAUUUUUCUCCAUCUUUUUUUUUCUUACAAAAGAAAUGCAAACAGAAAACAUAAACAAGAGCAAAAUCCCAUGUAAAUCUACCACUCAAUCAUGGCUAAUCUUUAAUAUCAUUGUUUUUUUCUAAAAUUGGGAGUUUGGGAUCACACUGGAUCUACUACUUGGUAACAGACUCUGAUCUUGUAACACAUUUCCAUUGUAAUUCUAUACCAUCAUUUUCAUGGCUAUAGACUUGGCCUAUAGCUGUGAAAGUAGAUUCACCAUAAUGGGAUCAGCCAAUCUCCUUUCCUUGGAUAUUAGGAUAUUUUCAAUUUUUUAUUUUCAUACAGACACUUAAGUGAAUGAAGCAAAAUGUCUGCACAUAUUCUUAGUUACCUAAAGGUAUGAUGUUAGAUUGUUUUUCUUCACUCAUAUUUUUACUACAUCAGAAUGUUGAUUACAGUUAUCUUUGAUGGUAUGAUGUGAGAUUAUUACUUUGUUUCCAUACUUAUUUUCUCUAAAUGCCUUGCAAUGAACAGGUUUUAUUUGCAUAAACACAAUAUUAUUUAAAAUGAUGCCAUGAAAAUUUCUAUAUGACCACCGUUUUCAUGGUAAUGGCUUGUUACGGCUGCCUGUAAUUCCACAUAGGGGAUAGGCCGUAAUUCACUUAACCAUCCCCUAUCAUUGACCGGCUGGGCUUUUUCUAAUGUCUUUAAGAUCGUUAUACAGGAAACCUACUCCAUAUCUGGGGUUACGUCCUCAGGGAGCAGCCCAGCAAAGGCUGGUGAACAGAUUUCACACCUUUGGUUCAUCCUGCCAAGCUGCUUUCCCGAAAAGAUGUUCCAAUUUCCCCUCCCACCGGCAGUGCGUGGGAAUGCCUGCCCAGCCGCCCUCCUCUCCCUGAGACGGUUCAGGCCCCUGGACAGUCGCAUCCUCUGCUAGGAGGGCAAGAGAAAGCAGGAAAUAAUUUGGCCAGCAAGUGACCCCAGACCCAGAGCCAGGAGUGAUUUUUAACAAGCCUGAUUCUCAGAACAGAACCUGCAGAGAAAAAGAAAGCAAGCAAGGAAAAAAAAAAAAAAACCCCUCUCUACUGGAAAAAACAUACACAUACACAGAUUAAAAUAAUAUUUGGCACUUACGUCGCACUUUUAAAAUUCUUCAAACGCUUUAUAAACACUAGCUAAUUAAUUAAGCCGCCUAAAUCUGGCUGCAGUCGGUGGAGAGAGCUCGAGAGGAGCUAAAAAAAAAAUGGGGGAGCCAGCGCUACACAACUCCAGAUUUUAUUGUCGCCUGCCUGGGGUGUGAUUACAGGCCUCCGGCUGCACCACAAGAAUAGCCCUGCUCCAACAUGCUGCACGCCUGACUCCGCAGCCUCUCCUGCGCCUCCUGCUCCCUCACCAACUGCUGACUCACAGCCCCUUGUGGUGUUAUUGAUAAGGAUAAUAAUAACUGCAAGCCAGGCUGAGUCCCGGGCUCCGGGCCUGCACCCUCCCCUGGAUAUGCCAGUAUCAACUCCACCUAACACAUGAAGAGAGAGGAGAUUUGCCCAGGGUCAUGGAGCCAACGACAUCCUUCCUUCCUUCAUUCAUUACCGCAUUCAUUCUGCAUAUUUUUAUCGAUGACACUGUGUUUUAGGCAGGAGGUUGGAAACAGUCCCUUGUGGAUCCUACAUCCUACUAUUGGGAAUGUGACAAUCCAGAGAAAAUCAAAUAUGUGAAUAAUACAGCUAUGUGAUAAUAAUGGGAAUAAGAAUUAAAACUUACCCAGCACCUAUGCAGCAGGCAUACCACCGUGUCAGGGUCCUCAUGACUGUGCUGGGGUGGAUGCCGGAACCCCACUUCAUGGAUGAUGGAAUGGGGGUCCAGGGAAGGUGGGUACAGAGGUGGCUAAGAGGGGAGCCAUGCUGUCACCCAGGCCUGCUGGCCCUAGCAACUGUGCUUCCCCGAGGCAGCCUUUCCAGUUGGUCCAGUCUCGAGGCUGAAAUACAGACCUAUCCGGAAAGUUCCUAGCUCAGUGCUGCUGGUGCUGCCUCUGAUGUCCCCGCCUGGAUGGGCCUCCCGGGCCUCCCACACAUUUGGCCACCAGCCUCACCCCUCUCAGGCCGUCUGAUGCUGGCUGGGCCUCUGUCCACUGUGGGUUCUGUCUGUCCACUGUGGGUUCUGUUUUUUUCUCCUGUGCCAUGAAGAUCUUGCCAUGUUCAACUUCAAAUGGAAAUGAAAUGAGAAGCUGGACUUCCUGAUAAUAAAAGCAGUUGAGGUCUUAAGUGGUUGAUCAGGAAAAGGAAGUCGAAAUGGUAAUAUUUACACCCAAAGCAGGUGGAGUGGUCUUAGGCACUCUGAGACUCCACUCACCUGCCAUGAGAACCGGGCCCCAAGGGUGAUCCCUUGCCAGAGUCAAGACUGGGUGAGGCUGGGAAUGGGAGAAAGAGGCAGGACAAUGGGCAGAUAGCCCUGGGCUUCCUGCAGUGAGGGCAGAUAGGGGUCUGUGAGCCUCUUUCCCUGGCUGCCCUGCCCCUGCCAGUGGGGUGGUGCCAGGCCAUGGGUUGGUGGGCAAAUUCACAGGGUCUCUCUCCUCCCCAGCCAGAGCCAGAGGGGCACAGCAGCUCUGGACAUCUGCCGCAGCCUUGUCUGAUGUACAAGGCAAAGGUGGCCCAGGUCAGGGCAGGACAAGGUCACAUGAAGGGUCAGUGGAGAGCCCAACUGGGGCCCCAGGUCACCUGUCACCUGCAUACCAGGUAGCUGCCACUCCUCUGUCUACCUGGUUCUCUCCUUCUCCCCUAUUCUAGCUCGCUCUCUCACUCUGCGUCUGUCUCUCAGGCAUGUGUUUCUCUGAGGUCUUUAUGAUCAUGAUCUUUCUUUUUUUUGUUUCUUGUACCUCACCUUGUUCAGAAUCGAGGCCCUGGCUCUGCCUUGCUCUGAACUGUUCUCACUUGGUCCCUAUCCAUCUUCAACGCAUCUCAUGACAAGCUCGUCCUGCCCUCUUCCUGUCUGGGCUCCCCCCGUGCACCCCAAUCUCUCCACCCAGGGUCCCUGUCUUGUGUGCCCCAGUGUCUCUGAUUGGGGCUCAGGCUCCUGCAGCCAACCUCUACAAUUCCUUCCAGCUGCCCAUUUGGGAGCCCUUGAGGCCUGGACUGGGUCCAGCUCCAGUGUGUCCCCAUCACAGUGAGGCCUGGAUCACAGGGCAUCAGCAGGUGUUGGUGAGAGUGAAGUUUGAGCCACAGCCACCUCCUUGUUUAUUCAAUGUAUAGUAACAACAACUUCCUCAGGGCCCAUCUCAGGGCUAAGUGACUUCUAUGUGUGAUCUCGUUUUCUUUUCAGAACAAAGCAGAGGCCUGGGGGCUGUUCUACCCAUCCUGUAGAUAAGAAAACUGAGACUCAAAACUGAUGGAUAAAUUAAGGUCCCACAAGAACAAGGGGCGAGCCAGGUUUCAAACCAGGUCCGAUGACUCUAAAGACCAGAUGCUGCAUUUGGACGCUGUCCCCAGCCUUGGCUUAUUUUAUCCUCCCAGAGAUCCAUCGAGGAGUGGCGGGUGAGGAGGAGCUGCAGGUGAUUCAGCCUGACAAGUCCGUGUUGGUUGCAGCUGGAGAGACAGCCACUCUGCGCUGCACUGCGACCUCUCUGAUCCCUGUGGGGCCCAUCCAGUGGUUCAGAGGAGCUGGACCAGGCCGGGAAUUAAUCUACAAUCAAAAAGAAGGCCACUUCCCCCGGGUAACAACUGUUUCAGACCUCACAAAGAGAAACAACAUGGACUUUUCCAUCCGCAUCGGUAACAUCACCCCAGCAGAUGCCGGCACCUACUACUGUGUGAAGUUCCGGAAAGGGAGCCCCGAUGACGUGGAGUUUAAGUCUGGAGCAGGCACUGAGCUGUCUGUGCGCGCCAAACCCUCUGCCCCCGUGGUAUCGGGCCCUGCGGCGAGGGCCACACCUCAGCACACAGUGAGCUUCACCUGCGAGUCCCACGGCUUCUCACCCAGAGACAUCACCCUGAAAUGGUUCAAAAAUGGGAAUGAGCUCUCAGACUUCCAGACCAACGUGGACCCCGUAGGAGAGAGCGUGUCCUACAGCAUCCACAGCACAGCCAAGGUGGUGCUGACCCGCGAGGACGUUCACUCUCAAGUCAUCUGCGAGGUGGCCCACGUCACCUUGCAGGGGGACCCUCUUCGUGGGACUGCCAACUUGUCUGAGACCAUCCGAGUUCCACCCACCUUGGAGGUUACUCAACAGCCCGUGAGGGCAGAGAACCAGGUGAAUGUCACCUGCCAGGUGAGGAAGUUCUACCCCCAGAGACUACAGCUGACCUGGUUGGAGAAUGGAAACGUGUCCCGGACAGAAACGGCCUCAACCGUUACAGAGAACAAGGAUGGUACCUACAACUGGAUGAGCUGGCUCCUGGUGAAUGUAUCUGCCCACAGGGAUGAUGUGAAGCUCACCUGCCAGGUGGAGCAUGACGGGCAGCCAGCGGUCAGCAAAAGCCAUGACCUGAAGGUCUCAGCCCACCCGAAGGAGCAGGGCUCAAAUACCGCCGCUGAGAACACUGGAUCUAAUGAACGGAACAUCUAUAUUGUGGUGGGUGUGGUGUGCACCUUGCUGGUGGCCCUACUGAUGGCGGCCCUCUACCUCGUCCGAAUCAGACAGAAGAAAGCCCAGGGCUCCACUUCUUCUACAAGGUUGCAUGAGCCCGAGAAGAAUGCCAGAGAAAUAACACAGGUACAGUCCUUGGACACAAAUGAUAUCACAUAUGCAGACCUGAACCUGCCCAAGGGGAAGAAGCCUGCUCCCCAGGCUGCGGAGCCCAACAACCACACGGAGUAUGCCAGCAUUCAGACCAGCCCGCAGCCCGCGUCGGAGGACACCCUCACCUAUGCUGACCUGGACAUGGUCCACCUCAACCGGACCCCCAAGCAGCCGGCCCCCAAGCCUGAGCCGUCCUUCUCAGAGUACGCCAGCGUCCAGGUCCCGAGGAAGUGAAUGGGACCGUGGUUUGCUCUAGCACCCAUCUCUACGCGCUUUCUUGUCCCACAGGGAGCCGCCGUGAUGAGCACAGCCAACCCAGUUCCCGGAGGGCUGGGGCGGUGCAGGCUCUGGGACCCAGGGGCCAGGGUGGCUCUUCUCUCCCCACCCCUCCUUGGCUCUCCAGCACUUCCUGGGCAGCCACGGCCCCCUCCCCCCACAUUGCCACAUACCUGGAGGCUGACGUUGCCAAACCAGCCAGGGAACCAACCUGGGAAGUGGCCAGAACUGCCUGGGGUCCAAGAACUCUUGUGCCUCCGUCCAUCACCAUGUGGGUUUUGAAGACCCUCGACUGCCUCCCCGAUGCUCCGAAGCCUGAUCUUCCAGGGUGGGGAGGAGAAAAUCCCACCUCCCCUGACCUCCACCACCUCCACCACCACCACCACCACCACCACCACCACUACCACCACCACCCAACUGGGGCUAGAGUGGGGAAGAUUUCCCCUUUAGAUCAAACUGCCCCUUCCAUGGAAAAGCUGGAAAAAAACUCUGGAACCCAUAUCCAGGCUUGGUGAGGUUGCUGCCAACAGUCCUGGCCUCCCCCAUCCCUAGGCUAAAGAGCCAUGAGUCCUGGAGGAGGAGAGGACCCCUCCCAAAGGACUGGAGACAAAACCCUCUGCUUCCUUGGGUCCCUCCAAGACUCCCUGGGGCCCAACUGUGUUGCUCCACCCGGACCCAUCUCUCCCUUCUAGACCUGAGCUUGCCCCUCCAGCUAGCACUAAGCAACAUCUCGCUGUGGACGCCUGUAAAUUACUGAGAAAUGUGAAACGUGCAAUCUUGAAACUGAGGUGUUAGAAAACUUGAUCUGUGGUGUUUUGUUUUGUUUUUUUUCUUAAAACAACAGCAACGUGAUCUUGGCUGUCUGUCAUGUGUUGAAGUCCAUGGUUGGGUCUUGUGAAGUCUGAGGUUUAACAGUUUGUUGUCCUGGAGGGAUUUUCUUACAGCGAAGACUUGAGUUCCUCCAAGUCCCAGAACCCCAAGAAUGGGCAAGAAGGAUCAGGUCAGCCACUCCCUGGAGACACAGCCUUCUGGCUGGGACUGACUUGGCCAUGUUCUCAGCUGAGCCACGCGGCUGGUAGUGCAGCCUUCUGUGACCCCGCUGUGGUAAGUCCAGCCUGCCCAGGGCUGCUGAGGGCUGCCUCUUGACAGUGCAGUCUUAUCGAGACCCAAUGCCUCAGUCUGCUCAUCCGUAAAGUGGGGAUAGUGAAGAUGACACCCCUCCCCACCACCUCUCAUAAGCACUUUAGGAACACACAGAGGGUAGGGAUAGUGGCCCUGGCCGUCUAUCCUACCCCUUUAGUGACCGCCCCCAUCCCGGCUUUCUGAGCUGAUCCUUGAAGAAGAAAUCUUCCAUUUCUGCUCUCAAACCCUACUGGGAUCAAACUGGAAUAAAUUGAAGACAGCCAGGGGGAUGGUGCAGCUGUGAAGCUCGGGCUGAUUCCCCCUCUGUCCCAGAAGGUUGGCCAGAGGGUGUGACCCAGUUACCCUUUAACCCCCACCCUUCCAGUCGGGUGUGAGGGCCUGACCGGGCCCAGGGCAAGCAGAUGUCGCAAGCCCUAUUUAUUCAGUCUUCACUAUAACUCUUAGAGUUGAGACGCUAAUGUUCAUGACUCCUGGCCUUGGGAUGCCCAAGGGAUUUCUGGCUCAGGCUGUAAAAGUAGCUGAGCCAUCCUGCCCAUUCCUGGAGGUCCUACAGGUGAAACUGCAGGAGCUCAGCAUAGACCCAGCUCUCUGGGGGAUGGUCACCUGGUGAUUUCAAUGAUGGCAUCCAGGAAUUAGCUGAGCCAACAGACCAUGUGGACAGCUUUGGCCAGAGCUCCCGUGUGGCAUCUGGGAGCCACAGUGACCCAGCCACCUGGCUCAGGCUAGUUCCAAAUUCCAAAAGAUUGGCUUGUAAACCUUCGUCUCCCUCUCUUUUACCCAGAGACAGCACAUACGUGUGCACACGCAUGCACACACACAUUCAGUAUUUUAAAAGAAUGUUUUCUUGGUGCCAUUUUCAUUUUAUUUUAUUUUUUAAUUCUUGGAGGGGGAAAUAAGGGAAUAAGGCCAAGGAAGAUGUAUAGCUUUAGCUUUAGCCUGGCAACCUGGAGAAUCCACAUACCUUGUGUAUUGAACCCCAGGAAAAGGAAGAGGUCGAACCAACCCUGCGGAAGGAGCAUGGUUUCAGGAGUUUAUUUUAAGACUGCUGGGAAGGAAACAGGCCCCAUUUUGUAUAUAGUUGCAACUUAAACUUUUUGGCUUGCAAAAUAUUUUUGUAAUAAAGAUUUCUGGGUAAUAAUGAGUCCUUCCGGUGUUCAGUAUUCUUGUCUUUGUGAGUGCGUCCCGGGGCCGCCUCGGGGCCUGCCUGCCCUCCUGCCAAAGCCUGGAAGAGGAUUGAAUGGACCCCAGGGUUUGGAAACAACCUACAGCAUUUGAGCCCCUCACGUAGGUUUUAGAGACGUACAAUUUUUGUUUGCCCUGGCUCAGAAGGAGCCGGUGUAAGGUUGAGAUAAAAUUCCAUAUAGACAACUGAGUUUGGAUCUCGGCUCUGCUGCUUUGUAGCUGUGGGAGUUCAAACAGCACCUCUUUGAGACUUGGGCCCCGCGUCGGCACAAUGGGGCAGGAAUAGUCCCUGCCAGGGUGACUGUGUGGAUUCAAGGAGGUUGGAAGCACUGAGCCCACGCUUGGCACUGGGUAGGCCAUCACUGAGGCUUGUGUCUUUCCUUCCUGCCCUGACCCUGCAUAGCUGAGUCUCGUGGCCUCUCACCACUGAUGGGAUCUCGGACACCCGGCUCACCCUCCUCCUGGGGCCUCACUUUCCUUCCCCACCAAAUGCAGACAUCUAAUGCUUGUCCUGUAAUAUCCUUGCCAGAUGACUGAUGUCAAGUGCUGGUUUAUAGUGGGUGCUCAAUAAAUGUUAGUUUCCUUUCUAUCCCUCCAUUAGAUCAUUAAUGAUAUUAGUGCUAAUUAUGUAAUAAAGUUAAGGCAUAAAUAUGUUAA